AGAGCGUGAGCCGCGACCUCCGCGCAGGUGGUCGCGCCGGUCUCCGCGGAAAUGUUGUCCAAAGUUCUUCCAGUCCUCCUAGGCAUCUUAUUGAUCCUCCAGUCGAGGUGAGUCUCCAUCCCGGGACCCGGGAGCCCUUCGCGCCCAGCUCCCUCUCCCCGGGAGCCGGGACGGCUCCCGGGACCCCAGCGGCCCCGCGUUCCUCGAGCCCCGCGCCCGCUUUGCCCCGGCCCUACCGCGGGCUGGCCGAGUCCCGCGUCCCCUCGAUGCGCGCCGGCCUCGGCCCGCCUCACUGUAGGAUGGGCUCCCGGGGUCCUUGAGGGGGAGCUCCAAAAGGAAGACAGGACGCCAGAAGGAAGACGGGACUCCAGUUCGCGGAUUCCCGCUCUCAGAAGCACUGCGGUGGCCUGGUGACAAGCACUCCUCGGAGUCUUGCGCAGGAACAGGGGAGCGGCCCCGGGGUGACCGGCCAGGGCAGGCUUCAGCUACUGGGGGGGCCGGAGGUGCAUUUUGAGAAGGGGGUGCGCGGGCUGAGGGAGCUUAGCUGCGCCAAAAAUGUGUGAGUGUUGCCUCGUGUGUUCUCUGCUGCUCACAUUUUUUUUAAGAGUGCCUACUGAGUUCCAGGCACUGCGCCAGGCAACUCUGACAUUACUUGCUUCCCAUGCCGCUGCUCCUGUUGGUGCCAGUCUCAGGCACGAGCUUUGGUUUAGUCUAAGGGUUCCCGCACCAGCUAUGCCCCCUCUCCACCGCUGACAGCCUCCCACUUCCUUAACUCAUCCCUAGACACCCUGCUGGGCCUUGGGCAGACUGGAGCCAGAGGCCAGGAAUAUUAUUCUCCUCUGAAGUCUGUGGUUUGGGCCGUAGAUUUCAAUCCCCUUCUCCCCUUUCAGGUUUCCCUUGAACAACCAUCUUCCCUCACACCUUCUCCUCGCCCUGAGACUUGGCUAGGAGGGUCGUGCCCUGGAUUUGUGGCUUUUUGGGGUGGAAGAUGACUGCUUCGUUUUGUUGUUGUUGUUUUGAGAUGGUUCCUGCUGUGUGUGAAGUGUCACAAAUUUGCAAGCUUCCUGAUCUGUGGAGCUUUCUCGAAGAUUCCAUGGCACUGGGCUUGUGUCUUGUUUGUCUGUUCUGGGGAGGGAGGGUGGCUUCUCUCCCUACCCCAGAUUGCGUUAGCUCAUCAGAGAAGGGGAUGUGUAGCUGCUUGCUGGCUCACUGGUGCCCUGGAGUGGGGCUAGCCUCAGCAGGAGCUUGAUAAAUGUCUUUCUAUGCGUGCUAGCAAUUUCCAGUCAUCCACAUCCCUCAAAAUGGGAUGUGGACUAGUUGAGAAAGCUGACGUGGUGACUGGCUAGGGCAAAAGAUGGCUCUGGGGUGGGGGAAAUAAGAAGGGGUGGUCAGAGAGGAAAACAGCAGGGAAAAGGGACUGGGGAAAUGGAAACUGCCCUUCAAGCAUAGCAACCUGUGGUGUCAGGAAAGAGCUGAGGAGGUGACAAUGGGGUGUACUGGGCCACACUGAACCAGAAGACCUCUCCCUGGUCCAGGCUUAGCCUCAAAUUAGUUGUGUGACUUGGGGCACAGUCCUUCCUCUAUCUGGGCCUCAGUUUGUCCAUCUGUAGAAUGAAAAAAAAGAUCUGAUUUAGAAAAAAAUCCAACAUCUUUUCUUAUGCGCCCCUCCCCCCCCCACUUCUCACACCACCAACAGUCGACUGUUUGGGAGGGGGUAGUGCAGAGAUUCAACUUCAUGCUGGACCAUUAUGUCUAGAGACAUGUGAAUGUCUGAAAAACUGCCCUGGAAAAUGCCACUAUUCCAAUGUGUGAGUGUUUUUCAAGUUUUUAUUCUGUCUAGCCCCGAAAGUGAGCUUAAUGGCUGGCUGGGGAAAGGUAUGCAUUGUCAGCAGCUCUUUAACCCCAAGGACCUCAAGAUGAGGUUUUGUUUUGUUUGUUUAUUGUUGUGUUUUUUUUUUUUAACUGGCAAAAGCCAAUUUUAGGAUUAAAGCCACCUUAUGACCCUCUGAUAUCAUUUUUAUUGCAGACCUAGUCUAGGGGCAGGAGGGCUUUGGUGGUCUCAGUGCUUUCAGGUUUAUUUGUUUGCCUCUGCACUUUUAAACUUGGGGCAGCGGGGAGGAUCUCGUCCAUGGAUUUCAGACAUCUGGGAGGGGCUGCUUCAGGCGUUUAGGUGGUCCUGUCUGGCAGUGCUCAGUCUACCACUGACUGCCAGUUCUGAUUGUGCCACGUUUCCAGCCACAUCACUCAUUUUACAGGGUCUCAGGGCUCCAUUUUUCCUCCUCUCUUCCCAUAGUCACUGGCCCUUAUCUUUUGAGAUGGCUGGGAGUUUGGCCUCAGGGAAAGAGGACAUCUUCUAGAUAUGGCAUUUGAAAGUAGAAACUGUAUUUUCCAAGCCCAGUUCUUCCCUCGCCCACAAUGGGAAGUAGCCACUUCAGACAUGAGAAAUGGUGUGGAUUUGGCACAUCUGUAUGCCACUUAAGCAAUUCUAACAGCUUGAAAUACUGCAGAAAAAAUGCAUUUUGCUUCUUAAGUUGGCAGUCCCUUGGUCCGCAAUACAGGGGUCAUGCCAACGUCUCUUGCCCUGUUUACCCCUUAUUUUAGGAAACAAAUUGCCUUAUGGCUUAAAAAAAUCCUUUUGGAAGUGUGACGUGCCAGUAGAAAAGCAUAGACAUCAUGAGUGAACAGCUCAGUGGCUUUUCACAAGUAAACAGGCCCGUGUAACCAACACCUAGAUCAGGAAAUACAGCAUUGCAACCCCCUCACCACACACACACACACACACACACACACACACACACACACACACACAGACACACACACACACACACACACACACACACACACGCAUGCAUCUCCAAAAUGCCUGUCCCCGUACACUUUCCUCCCCAAAGGAAACCACUCUCCUGCCUUCCAGUAUCACAGAUUAAUAUGGGACGAUGGCUUUUAAAAAGACUUUUAAUUAUAAUUUUUUAAAGACAUAUAAAGGUAGGGGGAACAGUGCACCCCCAUUGUUUGUGAACUCAUGGCCACUCUUAUUUUCUUUUACACCACCCACCCUCCAAUUCCAACUUAGAUUGUCUUGAAGCAUAUCUCAGACAUCAUAUCAUUUUAUAUGUAAUUGUUUUAGUAUGUAUUUCUAGUCAUUAAUAUUUCACAAACAUAAGAAAAUACCAUAAUUACACCAAAAAUUAAAGAAUAAUUUAUUCAUGUCUCAACUGUCCACUCAGUGUUCAAAUCUCUCCUAUUGUGUCAUAAAUGAUUUCUGUUUGUUUUUCAAGAGUUUGCUUUUAAAUAAAAUAAGAUCCAGAUAUUAGCAAGUGGGGCAUUUUGAUUUUUAAAAACACUUUUUAUGGAAUUAGAACAUGUAUACAGAGAAGUGCUCAAAUCAUAAGUGUACAGCUGAUGAGUUGUCAGAAUAUGACCACAGCGGUGUAAAGAAAGCCAAAUCAAGGACCCGAAUGUGAGCAGGACCUCAGAAGCCCCCUUUGUCACUGCCUCCCAGCAAAGGCAGCACUAUCCGGACUUCUAACACCAUCGGGUCGAGGGACCUCAGACUGAAUCAAAGAAUGAAGCCUCUUCCCGUGAUGUUGUCUAUGGCCCCCAGCCCCAGCCUCUGGAAAAUCAGCUCCUCUCUGAGGAAACAAAGUCAACUGAGACUGAGACUGGGAGCAGAGUUGGCAAACUGCCAGAAGCCUCUCGCAUCCUGAACACUAUCCUGAGUAAUUAUGACCACAAACUGCGCCCUGGCAUUGGAGGUGAGGAGCAGAACGACGUUCUUCCCCUCCUAGAGGGUCCAGGGGUUGAGGGCAUAGGCAUGGAGAAUGCACCUGGGCAGUAACAGAGGGUGCCAUGCUCAUGGACAGGAACAUCUGCUAUUGACCUGUCAGGUAAGAGAUAUUAACUCUAUUCUCAGCAGUGUCAUUGACCUUGAUCAAGACUUUUCCCUUCUCUCGCCCUCAGUUUUUCCAGUGGUAAAAUGAGAGGACUAAACUAGAUUGUUGAUCUUCAAGAUGUGUGUCCAAUUCUUAACAGUCCGUGAGCUUGGUUUUGCCAUGAAAGAAUAAAUAAAGAAAUAGGAUUAGAUGCUGAAACUGUGUGGUCCAACACUUACUUGACUCCCCUUUCAUCCCCUCUGACCACUUCCUCCCCCGUCCCAUGCGCCUGUUUGACACUUACCCUCUGCUGCUUCUGCUUCCCUUAUAGAGAAGCCCACUGUGGUCACUGUUGAGAUCUCCGUCAACAGCCUUGGUCCUCUCUCUAUCCUAGACAUGGAAUACACCAUUGACAUCAUCUUCUCCCAGACCUGGAAUUCUAAGAGGACCCACGAGCAUGAGAUCACCAUGCCCAACCAGAUGGUCCGCAUCUACAAGGAUGGCAAGGUGUUGUACACAAUUAGGAUGACCAUUGAUGCCGGAUGCUCACUCCACAUGCUCAGAUUUCCAAUGGAUUCUCACUCUUGCCCUCUAUCUUUCUCUAGCUUUUCCUAUCCUGAGAAUGAGAUGAUCUACAAGUGGGAAAAUUUCAAGCUUGAAAUCAAUGAGAAGAACUCCUGGAAGCUCUUCCAGUUUGAUUUUACAGGAGUGAGCAACAAAACUGAAAUAAUCACAACCCCAGUUGGUGACUUCAUGGUCAUGACGAUUUUCUUCAAUGUGAGCAGGCGGUUUGGCUAUGUUGCCUUUCAAAACUAUGUCCCUUCUUCCGUGACCACGAUGCUCUCCUGGGUUUCCUUUUGGAUCAAGACAGAGUCUGCUCCAGCCCGGACCUCUCUAGGGAUCACCUCUGUUCUGACCAUGACCACGUUGGGCACCUUUUCUCGUAAGAAUUUCCCGCGUGUCUCCUAUAUCACAGCCUUGGAUUUCUAUAUCGCCAUCUGCUUCGUCUUCUGCUUCUGCGCUCUGUUGGAGUUUGCUGUGCUCAACUUCCUGAUCUACAACCAGACAAAAGCCCAUGCUUCUCCUAAACUCCGCCAUCCUCGUAUCAAUAGCCGUGCCCAUGCCCGUACCCGUGCACGUUCCCGAGCCUGUGCCCGCCAACAUCAGGAAGCUUUUGUGUGCCAGAUUGUCACCACUGAGGGAAGUGAUGGAGAGGAGCGCCCGUCUUGCUCAGCCCAGCAGCCCCCUAGCCCAGGUAGCCCUGAGGGUCCCCGCAGCCUCUGCUCCAAGCUGGCCUGCUGUGAGUGGUGCAAGCGUUUUAAGAAGUACUUCUGCAUGGUCCCCGAUUGUGAGGGCAGUACCUGGCAGCAGGGCCGCCUCUGCAUCCAUGUCUACCGCCUGGAUAACUACUCGAGAGUUGUUUUCCCAGUGACUUUCUUCUUCUUCAAUGUGCUCUACUGGCUUGUUUGCCUUAACUUGUAGGUACCAGCUGGUACCCUGUGGGGCAACCUCUCCAGUUCCCCAGGAGGUCCAAGCCCCUUGCCAAGGGAGUUGGGGGAAAGCAGCAGCAGCAGCAGGAGCGACUAGAGUUUUUCCUGCCCCAUUCCCCAAACAGAAGCUUGCAGAGGGUUUGUCUUUGCUGCCCCUCUCCCCUACCUGGCCCAUUCACUGAGUCUUCUCAGCAGACCAUUUCAAAUUAUUAAUAAAUGGGCCACCUCCCUCUUCUUCAAGGAGCAUCCGUGAUGCUCAGUGUUCAAAACCACAGCCACUUAGUGAUCAGCUCCCUAAAACCAUGCCUAAGUACAGGCGGAUUAGCUAUCUUCCAACAAUGCUGACCACCAGACAAUUACUGCAUUUUUCCAGAAGCCCACUAUUGCCUUUGUAGUGCUUUCGGCCCAGUUCUGGCCUCAGCCUCAAAGUGCACCGACUAGUUGCUUGCCUAUACCUGGCACCUCAUUAAGAUGCUGGGCAGCAGUAUAACAGGAGGAAGAGAUCCCUCUCCUUUGGUCAGAUUAUUAUGUUCUCAGUUCUCUCUCCCUGCUACCCCUUUCUCUGCAGAUAGAUAGACACUGGCAUUAUCCCUUUAGGAAGAGGGGGGGGCAGCAAGAGAGCCUAUUUGGGACAGCAUUCCUCUCUCUCUGCUGCUGUGACAUCUCCCUCUCCUUGCUGGCUCCAUCUUUCGUCUGCACUACCAAUUCAAUGCCCUUCAUCCAAUGGGUAUCUAUUUUUGUGUGUGAUUAUAGUAACUACUCCCUGCUUUAUAUGCCACCCUCUUCCUUCUCUUUGACCCCUGUGACUCUUUCUGUAACUUUCCCAGUGACUUCCCCUAGCCCUGACCCAGGCACUAGGCCUUGGUGACUUCCUGGGGCCAAGAAACUAAGGAAACUCGGCUUUGCAACAGGCAUUACUCGCCAUUGAUUGGUGCCCACCCAGGGCACACUGUCGGAGUUCUAUCACUUGCUUGACCCCUGGACCCAUAAACCAGUCCACUGUUAUACCCGGGGCACUCUAACCAUCACAAUCAAUCAAUCAAAUUCCCUUAAAUUUGUAUGGCACUGGAACUUUGGCAAAGCACUUUUGACAAGUUGUGUCUGAUUGGAGCUUCAUGAUAGCCUUGUGACAUCUUUAGGGCAGGAUUCUUAUCCCCAUUUUGCAGAUGAAAACCCUGAGUCACAGAUUUCUGUGGGACUGUGGAUCUCACUGGAAGCUAUCCAAGAGCCCACUGUCACCUUCUAGACCACAUGAUAGGGCUAGACAGCUCAGUUCACCAUGAUUCUCUUCUGUCACCUCUGCUGGCACACCAGUGGCAAGGCCCAGAAUGGCGACCUCUCUUUAGCUCAAUUUCUGGGCCUGAGGUGCUCAGACUGCCCCCAAGAUCAAAUCUCUCCUGGCUGUAGUAACCCAGUGGAAUGAAUUUGGACAUGCCCCAAUGCUUCUAUAUGCUAAGUGAAAUCUGUGUCUGUAAUUUGUUGGGGGGUGGAUAGGGUGGGGUCUCCAUCUACUUUUUGUCACCAUCAUCUGAAAUGGGGAAAUAUGUAAAUAAAUAUAUCAGCAAAGCA